AGUGGCUGCCCGCACUGCGCCCGGGCGCUCGCCUUCGCUGCAGCUCCCGGUGCCGCCGCUCGGGCCGGCCCCCCGGCAGGCCCUCCUCGUUAUGGCCGCGGCCUCCUCCCCGCCCAGGGCCGAGAGGAAGCGCUGGGGUUGGGGCCGCCUGCCAGGCGCCCGGCGGGGCAGCGCGGGCCUGGCCAAGAAGUGCCCCUUCUCGCUGGAGCUGGCGGAGGGCGGCCCGGCGGGCGGCGCGCUCUACGCGCCCAUCGCGCCCGGCGCCCCAGGUCCCGCGCCCCCUGCGUCCCCGGCCGCGCCCGCCGCGCCCCCAGUUGCCUCCGACCUUGGCCCGCGGCCGCCGGUGAGCCUAGACCCGCGCGUCUCCAUCUACAGCACGCGCCGCCCGGUGUUGGCGCGCACCCACGUCCAGGGCCGCGUCUACAACUUCCUCGAGCGUCCCACCGGCUGGAAAUGCUUCGUUUACCACUUCGCCGUAUUCAAGAAAUUAAGCAUACGGUCACGAGAGUGCAAAGUUCUGUGAAACGCUCCAGUGGUUACACGCCCCGGGGUUUCAGCUUCGACCCUGGCUUCCUCAUCGUCCUGGUCUGCCUCAUCUUCAGCGUGCUGUCCACCAUCGAGCAGUAUGCCGCCCUGGCCACGGGGACUCUCUUCUGGAUGGAGAUCGUGCUGGUGGUGUUCUUCGGGACGGAGUACGUGGUCCGCCUCUGGUCCGCCGGCUGCCGCAGCAAGUACGUGGGCCUCUGGGGGCGGCUGCGCUUUGCCCGGAAGCCCAUUUCCAUCAUCGACCUCAUCGUGGUCGUGGCCUCCAUGGUGGUCCUCUGCGUGGGCUCCAAGGGGCAGGUGUUUGCCACGUCGGCCAUCAGGGGCAUCCGCUUCCUGCAGAUCCUGAGGAUGCUACACGUCGACCGCCAGGGAGGCACCUGGAGGCUCCUGGGCUCCGUGGUCUUCAUCCACCGCCAGGAGCUGAUAACCACCCUGUACAUCGGCUUCCUGGGCCUCAUCUUCUCCUCGUACUUUGUGUACCUGGCUGAGAAGGACGCGGUGAACGAGUCAGGCCGCGUGGAGUUCGGCAGCUACGCAGAUGCGCUGUGGUGGGGGGUGGUCACAGUCACCACCAUCGGCUAUGGGGACAAGGUGCCCCAGACGUGGGUCGGGAAGACCAUCGCCUCCUGCUUCUCUGUCUUUGCCAUCUCCUUCUUUGCGCUCCCAGCGGGGAUUCUUGGCUCGGGGUUUGCCCUGAAGGUGCAGCAGAAGCAGAGGCAGAAGCACUUCAACCGGCAGAUCCCGGCGGCAGCCUCACUCAUUCAGACCGCAUGGAGGUGCUAUGCUGCCGAGAACCCCGACUCCUCCACCUGGAAGAUCUACAUCCGGAAGGCCCCCCGGAGCCACACUCUGCUGUCACCCAGCCCCAAACCCAAGAAGUCUGUGGUGGUAAAGAAAAAAAAGUUCAAGCUGGACAAAGACAAUGGGGUGACUCCUGGAGAGAAGAUGCUCACAGUCCCCCAUAUCACGUGCGACCCCCCAGAAGAGCGGCGGCUGGACCACUUCUCUGUCGACGGCUAUGACAGUUCUGUAAGGAAGAGCCCAACACUGCUGGAAGUGAGCAUGCCCCAUUUCAUGAGAACCAACAGCUUCGCCGAGGACCUGGACCUGGAAGGGGAGACUCUGCUGACACCCAUCACCCACAUCUCACAGCUGCGGGAACACCAUCGGGCCACCAUUAAGGUCAUUCGACGCAUGCAGUACUUUGUGGCCAAGAAGAAAUUCCAGCAAGCGCGGAAGCCUUACGAUGUGCGGGACGUCAUUGAGCAGUACUCGCAGGGCCACCUCAACCUCAUGGUGCGCAUCAAGGAGCUGCAGAGGAGGCUGGACCAGUCCAUUGGGAAGCCCUCACUGUUCAUCUCCGUCUCAGAAAAGAGCAAGGAUCGCGGCAGCAACACGAUCGGCGCCCGCCUGAACCGAGUAGAAGACAAGGUGACGCAGCUGGACCAGAGGCUGGCACUCAUCACCGACAUGCUUCACCAGCUGCUCUCCUUGCACGGUGGCAGCACCCCCGGCAGCGGCGGCCCCCCCAGAGAGGGCGGGGCCCACAUCACCCAGCCCUGCGGCAGUGGCGGCUCCGUCGACCCUGAGCUCUUCCUGCCCAGCAACACCCUGCCCACCUACGAGCAGCUGACCGUGCCCAGGAGGGGCCCCGAUGAGGGGUCCUGAGGAGGGGAUGGGGCUGGGGGAUGGGCCUGAGUGAGAGGGGAGGCCAAGAGUGGCCCCACCUGGCCCUCUCUGAAGGAGGCCACCUCCUAAAAGGCCCAGAGAGAAGAGCCCCACUCUCAGAGGCCCCAAUACCCCAUGGACCAUGCUGUCUGGCACAGCCUGCACUUGGGGGCUCAGCAAGGCCACCUCUUCCUGGCCGGUGUGGGGGCCCCGUCUCAGGUCUGAGUUGUUACCCCAAGCGCCCUGGCCCCCACAUGGUGAUGUUGACAUCACUGGCAUGGUGGUUGGGACCCAGUGGCAGGGCACAGGGCCUGGCCCAUGUAUGGCCAGGAAGUAGCACAGGCUGAGUGCAGGCCCACCCUGCUUGGCCCAGGGGGCUUCCUGAGGGGAGACAGAGCAACCCCUGGACCCCAGCCUCAAAUCCAGGACCCUGCCAGGCACAGGCAGGGCAGGACCAGCCCACGCUGACUACAGGGCCGCCGGCAAUAAAAGCCCAGGAGCCCAUUUGGAGGGCCUGGGCCUGGCUCCCUCACUCUCAGGAAAUGCUGACCCAUGGGCAGGAGACUGUGGAGACUGCUCCUGAGCCCCCAGCUUCCAGCAGGAGGGACAGUCUCACCAUUUCCCCAGGGCACGUGGUUGAGUGGGGGGAACGCCCACUUCCCUGGGUUAGACUGCCAGCUCUUCCUAGCUGGAGAGGAGCCCUGCCUCUCCGCCCCUGAGCCCACUGUGCGUGGGGCUCCCGCCUCCAACCCCUCGCCCAGUCCCAGCAGCCAGCCAAACACACAGAAGGGGACUGCCACCUCCCCUUGCCAGCUGCUGAGCCGCAGAGAAGUGACGGUUCCUACACAGGACAGGGGUUCCUUCUGGGCAUUACAUCGCAUAGAAAUCAAUAAUUUGUGGUGAUUUGGAUCUGUGUUUUAAUGAGUUUCACAGUGUGAUUUUGAUUAUUAAUUGUGCAAGCUUUUCCUAAUAAACGUGGAGAAUCACAGGCUGGGCUGGGCACUGCUCUCACCUUGGUUCCUGGGGCAUCCAUGGGGUCUCUCACAGACAGGACCCCUGCAGUUCCCCUGGAAGCAGUGCCCAGGUGGCUGUGGAAUAGGAA